GAAGCUGUCAUGGCUGCUCCUGUACGUAGUCACGGUCUUGUGCUCUAAGGUGAGUGGAGGACGAGCUUGGGCUUAGCGGCAGCCCGUAUCACAUCCUAGACUUUUUACUUCGAGGAGAAGAGUCUCACGAGUUGUCCUGGAAGUAAGUUUAAAGGAGGAAAACGACAGCACGUGUUCUUUUUCACUAGUAGAAGUGACGUUGGUUUCAUGUUGACAACUUUGAAGCCAUUUGGAAGUGUUUCAGUGGAGAGCAAAAUGAAUAACAAAGCGGGCUCCUUUUUCUGGAACCUUAGACAAUUCAGUACAUUAGUUUCAACAAGCAGAACUAUGAGGCUAUGUUGUUUGGGACUUUGCAAACCAAAAAUAGUUCAUUCAAACUGGAACAUUUUAAAUAACUUUCAUAACAGAAUGCAAUCAACUGAUAUCAUUAGAUAUCUCUUUCAGGAUGCAUUCAUUUUUAAAUCAGAUGUUGGCUUUCAAACAAAGGGCAUAAGCACUCUAACAGCCCUUAGAAUUGAAAGACUACUUUAUGCUAAAAGACUGUUUUUUGACUCAAAGCAGUCUCUUGUCCCUGUUGAUAAAUCUGAUGAUGAAUUGAAGAAAGUAAACCUUAAUCAUGAAGUCUCCAAUGAAGAUGUUCUUACCAAGGAAACAAAACCAAACCGUAUCAGCAGUAGAAAACUGUCUGAGGAAUGUAAUUCCCUGAGUGAUGUGUUAGAUGCAUUUUCAAAAGCGCCCACAUUUCCUAGUAGCAACUAUUUCACAGCAAUGUGGACAAUUGCCAAAAGACUGUCUGAUGACCAGAAGCGCUUUGAAAAACGACUGAUGUUUAGCCACCCUGCAUUUAAUCAGCUCUGUGAACAUAUGAUGAGAGAAGCCAAGAUCAUGCAGUAUAAGUACCUACUGUUCAGUCUUCACGCCAUAGUGAAGCUUGGAAUCCCUCAGAACACUAUUUUGGUGCAGACUUUGCUGAGGGUGACCCAGGAACGUAUCAAUGAGUGUGAUGAGAUAUGCCUUUCAGUUUUGUCAACUGUUUUAGAGGCAAUGGAACCAUGCAAGAAUGUUCAUGUUCUACGAACGGGAUUCAGAAUACUAGUUGAUCAGCAAGUUUGGAAAAUAGAAGAUGUCUUCACAUUACAAGUUGUGAUGAAGUGUAUUGGAAAAGAUGCACCGAUUGCUCUUAAGAGGAAACUGGAGAUGAAAGCCUUGAGGGAAUUAGACAGAUUUUCUGUUUUGAAUAGCCAACACAUGUUUGAAGUACUAGCUGCCAUGAAUCACCGAUCUCUUAUACUCCUGGAUGAAUGCAGUAAGGUGGUCCUAGAUAAUAUCCAUGGGUGUCCUUUAAGAAUAAUGAUCAACAUAUUGCAGUCCUGCAAAGACCUCCAGUACCAUAAUUUGGAUCUCUUCAAGGGACUUGCAGAUUAUGUGGCUGCAACUUUCGACAUCUGGAAGUUCAGAAAAGUUCUUUUUAUCCUCAUUUUAUUUGAAAACCUUGGCUUUCGACCUGUUGGUUUAAUGGACCUGUUUAUGAAGAGAAUAGUAGAGGAUCCUGAAUCCCUAAACAUGAAAAACAUUCUAUCUAUUCUUCAUACUUACUCUUCUCUCAAUCAUGUCUACAAAUGCCAGAACAAAGAACAGUUCGUGGAAGUUAUGGCUAGUGCUCUGACUGGUUAUCUUCACACUAUUUCUUCUGAAAACUUAUUGGAUGCAGUAUAUUCAUUUUGCUUGAUGAAUUACUUUCCCCUGGCUCCUUUUAAUCAGCUUCUGCAAAAAGACAUCAUCAGUGAGCUGCUGACAUCAGAUGACAUGAAGAAUGCUUACAAGCUGCAUACUUUGGAUACUUGUCUAAAACUUGAUGAUACUGUCUAUCUGAGGGACAUAGCCUUGUCACUCCCACAGCUGCCGCGGGAGCUGCCAUCGUCACAUACAAAUGCAAAGGUGGCAGAGGUGCUGAGCAGCCUUCUGGGAGGUGAAGGACACUUCUCAAAGGAUGUGCACUUGCCACACAAUUAUCAUAUUGAUUUUGAAAUCAGAAUGGACACUAACAGGAAUCAAGUGCUACCACUUUCUGAUGUGGAUACAACUUCUGCUACAGAUAUUCAAAGAGUAGCUGUGCUAUGUGUUUCCAGAUCUGCUUAUUGUUUGGGUUCAAGCCACCCCAGAGGAUUCCUUGCUAUGAAAAUGCGGCAUUUGAAUGCAAUGGGUUUUCAUGUGAUCUUGGUCAAUAACUGGGAGAUGGACAAACUAGAGAUGGAAGAUGCAGUCACAUUUUUGAAGACUAAAAUCUAUUCAGUAGAAGCUCUUCCUGUUGCUGCUGUAAAUGUGCAAAGCACACAAUAAAGUGAAAAUCAACCUUUUCAUAUUAGGAGACAUGCAUUUGUAAAAAUUAAUAAAGAUGACAAGUCAGUUGUCAAUGGAAUUGAGCUAUCUGCUAAGACAAAAAAUGUUACCUCAGUUCACUAUUAAAAUUAAUUUUAGGAGUGGAAGAAAUGUUGUUACUGCCAUUUAAAAAUAUGCUGAGAAAAUUCCAGAAGGGUUAUUUUUCCAACCACACCUAUUCCCUCUAGUGCCCAGAUAUUUGAUUUGUGAGCUGUACGUUUCACCUUUUCAUCUUUGAUCUACUAAAAACUGGUUUCUUAGUUGUGAGGUGUCACAGGCAGGUUGAUGUGGGUAGUAGUCCUUGUCUUUGGAAUCUGAAUAUUUAUACUCCUGCUCUAAGCUGUUCUAAGACUUGGGGUUAUGCCUUUAAAUCAUUUUCAAGCAUUGGCCAAAUAAUAAUUGGACAAAGUUCUAAAGUUGUCAAGUGUGUAAGAAUUAGUGAGGUAGCUGUUGAAAAUGAGUGAGGAUGGUAUUUGUAUUUGUAAUAAGCACUGCAGGUAGAGAUAUUUCAUGGGUUAUAAUAAGAGAAACACAGAUGAGAUGUAGAUGGUAAGGAGUCUUACUGUUGUUGGGGUCCUUCCUUUCUCUUUCUUUUUUCCCCCUUACCCCUCCCACAAUUUCAUGAAGUCUUUUAAAUUAAAUAUAUAGCUGAAUUGUGUUGUGAAUCAGACCUGAGGACUAUUUUUUCGAUUAUGUGUGUUCAUUCUUUGUUCAAAUAUUUGUCCAAAUUCAACUAUUUUGUUCAAUAUGCCUGUCUACCUAGUAUUUGGCUCGCUGGGGAUAUAGUGAUGAAUAGGCAUGGUCUCUUGUGGAACUUACAGCAUGGGUUCCAUGCAAGUUGGUGUUAUUCUGCCCCCAAGCACACAGACAUGCAAUUACUAGACAUCUUAGUAUGUGCCGGGCACUGCUAAGUAUUCAUUUGUGUGCUGCCUUUUCAUGAUCUGAACCCUUUGAGGUGUAGCUGCUAUUAUGAUUCUCUCUGUGUCUUCACUUCCUCAUCUCUAAAAUCAGGAUAGGUAUUUGCCCAAGGCUACACAGAGUAGGGGAGGGCUGGAGUUUGAAUGUGAGCUAACAUAGGCUUAUAAGAAAAUACAAAAACUGGGCUGGGCACGGUGGCUCGUGCUUGUCAUCCCAGCACUUGGGAGGCCGAGGUGGGCUGAUCAUGAGGUCAGGAGGUCAAGACAAUCCUGGCCAACACGGUGAAACCCCAUCUCUACUAAAAUACAAAAAAUUAGCCGGGCAUGGUGGUGCAUGCCUAUAAUCCCAGCUACUGGGGAGGCUGAGGCAGGGGAAUCGCUUGAACCCGGGAGGUGGAGAUUGCAGUGAGCCAAGAUGGUCCUGCUGCACUCCAGCCUGACCACAGAGCGAGACUCUGUCUCAAAAAAAAAAAAAAAAAAAAAAAAAAAAAAAUACAAAAACUAUAGCAAUAUGACAACAGCUGCCAGGUUGUAUCAAUUUAUCCAGCUUGCAUUUAGAAAAGGUUAGAGCUGAAAGGAAAUUUAGUGAUUAUUUAAUUGUUACUUCCCUCAUUUUAUGGACGAGGAAGAUAAGGCUCAAAGAAUUUUCCUUUCCUGAAGUCUCAGCUAUGCCAUUGGUUCCACAUCAUUUCAUCCUCACCUGCUCUUCAGCUUGUGUCCCAGGAGAUCAGGCUUCUGGUUCCAGAUUGGACAACCUCUAGUUUUGUAUACUUGGCCAAGUGAUUUAACCUUAUAAGCUUCAGAACAAGAUGCAGAUAUUCUGUUAUUAAAGGAACUAAGGUUUUGUCUUUAAAUGUUGAGUGUGCAUCAGUUUUGAGUGUCUAAUUAUGACUCCUCUUCAAAGGAUUUGACAAAUUUGUGAAUAUUUAUGACCACCUUUUAGGGUAGUAAUUUUCAGUUUGUACUAGUUAACCUGGCAGAUAAAAAGGCAUCCCUCUUUUACUAGCAUUCUAGUGUUAGCAUUCUUCAUUGCUUUGUGUCAAUGAAAGAAAAAUGGGCAAAGAGCUGAUGAACAUGAAAAAAGUUCAGUCUACUUGUAAAGACAUGCACAUUGAAACAGAAGAGAUGGUUUUGCCUUUCAAAUUAGCAGUUUUUUUUCUUUUAAGAAUUACAGUGCUGAUGAAGGUAUAAUGAGGCAAGCACUUGCAUAAGCUGUUGGUAGACUGUAAAUUAAUACCUUUCUGGAAUGUACUUUGUGGGGUUUUCUUCUCCCAUAAUUUAAAAAAUAGCUUUAUUAUAGUAUAAUUGACAUACAGUAAACUGCAUAUAUUUAAAGUGUACCGUUAGGUCAGUUUUGACGUACAUACACACACACACACAUCUGUGAAACCACAAUCAAGAUAAUGAAUAUAUCUAUCACCUCUAAAAGGUUCCUGUCUUUGCUUUUUUCUCUGUCCCCUAAACAACCACUGAUCUAUGGCACACAUAGAAAAAAAUUAGGAAAUAUAUUAAAUGCUCAUUUUGUGUGAGAUAUCCAAAUAUUUUUUUCAGAAUCCCUAAUGAAAAGGUUGAUCUUGCUCUAGAUACAAGAUAUAAAAUUGUAUUCUUGAAAUAGCUACAUGCAAUUCUUUUUUAUUAUUUUUUAAUUUUAAUUUUUAGAUUUUUAAAGAUGGGGCCCUGCUAUGUUACCCAGGCUAGCUUCAAACUCCUGGGCUCAAGGGAUCCUCCUGCCUCAGCUUCUCAAGUAGAUAGGACUGAUUAUAGGUACAGGCUACUGUGCCCAGCUCAAUUCUUGAUUGAGACAUUUACCAGCUCUCCGAAUUCUCAGUAGUUACCACUGAAUAGAAACUUUCUUUACACAAAGCUGAUUAAACAGUUUAGAACUUUUAAAAAACAUUCAAAAAUUGAAAAUUUCAUAUAUACAUAGCCUAACAACUCUUCUUGUCAUUGACAAAAUGUGAUGGUAUUUUUUUUGUGAUAAUACACAUGGACCUCAAAUGCAAUUGAACUAUUCAUAUCAAGUAUUUCCAAAUAACAAUGACAUUCCAAUUUAUAGAAUGUCAUGUGUUGUGAGGGUAGUCACCCUGCAACUGGCUUGGACAUCUCUAAGCAAAUAGAAGUUUCUGUAAGAUAGAGAUUUGGGGCAUCUACUUGGAACUACCUAUGAGGAGCUGGCAUUCCUCAAAUCCCAACUGACUGCACUUUUCCAUGAAAUUACCCAGCAGUUAUGAUGGUCAGUGGCUCACUCAGCAGCAAGCCACUUAGGUAGCUGGCGAGGGACGUGGCACAGCCUUGUCUUCACACAGCACAUCACAGCCAGGCAGCAAAGGACAGAUCUCUCUCAUACUCUUCAUUCACAGGGCCUGAGAGGUGGACCAUCAGACUCCACCCUGUUUUGCGCUGACUUGUAGGGAGACCUAGGUGUGGAGCUUCCUGGCCAGGAGGGCAGUGGCUGCCCAGAAGGCAGGAGAUGGCUAUCUCUUUUUUUUUCCUGAGACGGAGUCGUGGUCUGUCGCCCAGGCUGGAGUGCUGUGGCGUGAUCUCAGCUCACUGCAAGCUCCGCCUCCUGGGUUCAAGCCAUUCUCCUGCCUCAGCCUCCCGAGUAGCUGGGACUACAGGUGCCCACCUCCAUGCCCGGCUAAUUUUUGUAUUUUUAGCAGAAACAGGGUUUCACCAUGUUAGCCAGGAUGGUCUCGAUCUCCUGACCUUGCGAUCUGCCCGCCUUUGGCCUUCCAAAGUGCUGGGAUUAUAGGCGUGAGCCACCACCCCCGGUCCAAGAUGGCUAUCUCUUAACACACUUGUAACCCAUUUGUGCACACAGGUGUGCCGUGACUCACUGGUGGAUCCAAAAAAAGCUGAAGCCUACAUUUCCCAGAGCCCCUUUCAGCUUGAAUUCCAAAUGUGACUUAGCUUCCUCUAUGCAGAUGUACCUACUUGAAACUGGGAAGGCCAAAUGAGAUAGAGGUAAUGUUUCUGCCAACAAACAGCCACAGAGCAUUUUAUUUUUCUAGAAGAGCAAUAACAGAGACCCCAGGGUGUGGUGUGGCAGGACGAGGAGCAUCCAUUUUGCUGGUGGGGAUUGUGGCUAAAAUAAUGUGGCUCUGGAGCCAGCAAUGGGCAGCAUCUUCAUGACUUUCCAGCUUCCAGGCUGUAAGCAGAGAUAGCAUCUCUUCUGGACAGCCAGUUAUGUGAUAGUGUUCUGAGAGUCAUUCCUGGAAGUCAGACUAAAGGCUGCUCCUUCAGCCUUUCCAUUCAUCUUGUAAGCAGGAGGCUUCUGUGCAUGGCCAGAAACUAACAAAAGCACAUUGUGUCUAAACUAGGUUGCAGUGGUUUCUGUUAUCAGCAAGUAAAUCCUGAUUGAUAAAGAUACUACAAUAUAUGCACAUAUAUAUGUUAUAGAAUCAAUAAAAAUUGGAUACUUUGCUUUAAAA